GUUGCGGAGCUCUGAAGCGGCUCCCUGAGGGCGCUGGUUUUGAACUGGUCUUGUGCGGUUUGCGCUUUCUCUUAGUGGUUACAGUUGGCGCUGUCUCCGCUUUCCUGUUUCGUGGCGGGCAUCUUGGCCAAAACACUCUCCCUGCCACCUUAUUCCUCUAGGGUUGUGAUUUUUUUCUUUCACCAAGAAAUAUCACUCGCUGGUAAUUUGUCAAACUGAAGAAACCCCUGAAGAAGCAGUGGUGGGCAGGCGCCGACGCUGCGGCUUCCAGAGCAUUUUGGCAAAUCAAAGCCAGGGACCGUUGCUGGGCCUCAUUUCCGCAACUUUUCGGCUCCGAACUGCUUCUUUGACUUAGAAGAUAUCUUAUCCUGCCGUUGUAAUGGCAGCUGAACUGCGAAUGAUACUUUAUGAAGAUGAUUCAGUACAAGUACAAUAUGUUGAUGGUUCCACAUUGCAACUUUCUCCCUGUGGCUCUGAAUUUUUAUUUGAAAAGUCACCACCUGUUUCAGCACAUCCUUUAGAACAACCAGAAAGAAUUCGUCAAAGGACACAUUUUGUCAUUAGCACUUACAGAGAGCAACUACAGCGAGCCCUAGAUUUUCGAAACUCUUCAGCUACUUGCCCUUUUUUAUCUGAAACCAUCAUACCUUCUGAAAGAAAAAAGCAUAUCUUCAUUGACAUAACAGAAGUGAGAUGGCCCAGUCUUGAUACAGAUGGUACCAUGAUAUAUAUGGAGAGUGGCAUUGUGAAGAUAACAUCUUUAGAUGGUCAUGCAUACCUCUGCCUGCCCAGAUCUCAGCAUGAAUUUACAGUACAUUUUUUGUGUAAAGUUAGCCAGAAGUCAGACUCAUCUGCAGUGUUGUCAGAAACAAAUAAUAAAGCCCCAAAAGAUAAACUAGUUGAAAAAACUGGCAAAAUCUGUAUACGUGGAAAUUUACCAGGACAGAGACUGAAGAAUAAAGAAAAUGAGUUUCAUUGCCAGAUCAUGAAAUCCAAAGAAACUUUAAAGAAGAUGAGUUGUGUAAAUGGAACUGAAGGGAGGGAAGAGCUGCCUUCGCCUGGUACAAAGCACACAUGUGUAUACACAUGGGUCAAGCAGUGCUGGUCUGUGGCUGCCUGUCCAGAGGAAUGGAAAUAUCCUUUGUCUUUAGCACUUCAUUUUCAUAAUAAAAUCAGCAAUAUGUCUAAAAUUGAUGCACAUAUAACUCAGAGUAGAUUUUUAACUUCUGAUAUUUCAGAGGAAAGAGGAAAAGUGGUUUCUGUUCUUCCCAGGGCCCUGUCACUCAGCUGUCCAGUCCCACACCUACACAGGUGGAAUUUUUGUGAUUCACUUUUACAGAGACAAUCUGAUGAAUAUUCCUAUCCUGAACUAGUGAAAAUGGUUUGGUACAAAGGUGUUACAUAUAGACUUACCCAUCAAAAUAUGAACUCAAUAGAGAUUUAUUCUGGGGAUGGAUCUGUUUUCAAAUCAGAAGGGGCUUAUUUUGGGAACUAUUUUACUUAUUAUUCUAUUCAAGAAGGAUCAGGAAAGAGAGAAGAGAAAACUUACUCAGUAAAUAACCUUCCUCCAGAUAGACCGGGAAGUCCAUUCACUGUCGGUUCUCUAAUUAAACAGGCAACAAGAAUUCUUCAACAUUGUGUGAAGAUGAGACUUUCUUUAAGCCAUAACUAUCGUAUAUGCUGCUGGAAAAUGGUACCUGGGAUAAAUGAUAGCAAUAUACUGCCUUUGGUUUUGAAAGAGUCACUCAUACCCAGUGUGGGAAGAUUUCUUGCCUACUCUGAUGACAAAGUACAUGCUAUCUUUUUAGAUGGCAUUACUCUAACCCUAAAUUGGAAUUUCAGCUCUCCUAUUGAGAAGAGACAGGUAAAUCAAGGUCUUAACUUAGGUUGGUGUAAGUUAACUUUUCCUGAUGGACAAGAGCAGUUAAUUCAGAUUGAACACCCUGAACCAUAUGAAAGAUAUGUGACAACAGUAACAUCAUGGUGCAGGAGACUGACCCAGACUAGUCCCAGAGAGAUGCCCACUCAUUCGUCAUCUUCUGUUCUCCAAGAAAAUUGGCUGGAGUACAAGGGAAAGAGUACAAGCUGACAGGGAGGUGCAUGUGAUCUGUUGUAGUAAAGCCAAUAAAGCAGACAAGUCACACAACCUACUACGAACUGUGAAGAUUUUUCUGGUGACUUGAAUAUUUUAGACUAAUGUCUUCAUUAAUUUUGCAGAGAGCUAGUCAAGUUACAGUUUGUAGUUGUAUGCCAUUGCUCAUAUUUCAUUCUAACUUGAUAAGAAAAAGGAUAAAGAACACACACUUAGGGGUUCUGCUGGAGACGUAUAUAUUAGCCCUCUACUCCAUACCAGUUGUCCCACUAUCUUUCUAUAGAACAUGGUAUAAGAGCUAAUGUUCAUCAUGUUAACCCUCUGUGCUUAAAAAAACAAUGAAAUAAGUAGGUAGUCUAUUCCAGAAAGAAUUUAAUAAAAAAUAGUUGUUUUGACACGUAAUUCAACUAUUUAAAAACUUGGAUCUCCCAUACCAUCCAUUCCCAAAGAGUUCCAUAUAAAUGAGGUCUUAAUAUAUGCACAAGUACAGAAAAGUAAAAAAUCCUUUCUUCUGAGAGAAACAAUCUAGGUAGGAAGAGCAGGAAGUUAAAUAGUUCAAGAGAAGAUAUUACAAAUAAGUAUGUGAUUAAUUAAUAUGCUAUAGGAAUUCAAGGAAGGAGAGAGCAGUUCUUUCACAGAAGGAAUGGGAUUUUAAUAGGUUUGUAAAGUUUGCGUAAACUUUAGGGAGGAAAGUAGAGUGUAAGCUAGGUUAGUACUAAGAAGUAACAGGAAGGCCCAUUAUCCUCAAACAUCAAUAUUUGAUUACAAAUUCCUUGAAGUGGAUUUACAAGGGGUAGACUUUUAUUCACUUACCUUUAAAGGCACUCAGUAAGUAUCAGUUGAGUCAAGUUGAUUUGUUGCUAAAUAAAGGUAACAUAAAGAGAAUUCUUCUGCGUUCUUCCGUUUAAAAUUCUAAUGAAAAAAAAAGUCAGGUAUGCUUAUUUGAAAUAUCAUGAAUACAAAAGAAUCAGACAACUGAAUGAAUUUUUUCUUUUUCCUUGGACAGGUCUGUUGCUUCUGAACUUGAAAAGAUACAGAAGUUUAACUGUAUCCUUUAAACAGAAUGCACUGUCCUACAUAAUUACUCUCUUUCAUUCUAGGCUUAAUUCAUGACUUCAGUACUUUGUGAAUAUUAAUCUAUACUUAAUAUAUUGCUAACCUUUAUUGAGUCAGCAAAUACCUAAGAUUGUAAUUUAAGAUGGAUCUUGUCCAUAGAAGGUAUAGCAUGUUAACAUUUAUACUUUUCUUUGAGUUUAAAUUGGGCAAAGAACAGUUAAUUAGGGUUAAGGUCUCCUUUGGAGACUUUUUCACUUACAUAAUUAUAUAAUAAAAUUAUAACUGUUUAAGACCUCUUUUUUUAAAUGAAAUAUUUCAUUCUGUACAUUCUCACCCAAUUCAUCUAAAUUUGUUUUCUCUUGUGGUUUUUCUCUAAUCUUAUUCAAAUAAGUUAGUUCUAUAGCGAACAGGUUUUUCACUCUAAAUCUUUUUAAAUUAAAAAUAGACACUACACAGAUUCCUUAUAAUCCUGUCAUCCUACUCUUUAAUUCCCGUGUCAUUUCUUCACUUAAAGAAAUGUUACUGAAAUUUUCAUUUCCUCCUUACCACCAAACCUCCACCCAAACACACACAUACACACUCUAUUCUCUUUCCCCCUCCCUUAUACUGUAAUUAGUUUCUUCAUCUACAAGGAGCAGACUUGAUAAGCCUUGCAGUUCCAACUGUAUUAUGAAUCCAAGAGGUCUUCCAGCUGAGAAAUAUUUUAAUAUGAAGCCUAUGCUUUCUGUAUAUAAAGAUAUUUAUAUAGUGAAAAAUGUGGGGAAAACCUCCUUAACUAAGCAACUUAGUGCUACUAGAAAAUAGUGGUAUCCUAAACCAGAUUUCUAACAAGAAAAAUGAACAACAGUCUUUUGAUCAUUAUAAACCAGGAUCUUCAGAAACCUUGCUAGGAGAAGUUAAUGAAAAUAGAGUAUCAAUAGCAUUGAAAAAAACCUCUGAAAUCCUUCACGAUAUUGACUGUCUUCUAUCAAACUCUAAAAAGUGAAAAAUGGAAUUAUUACAACAUAUUAUUAAAGUUUAAGGAUGUUGUUUCAAGUGACUGGUAUAAAAUUACUAGUAAGCCAAGAUAUUGUACGUAUUACCCCGGCACAAUGAUUGUGAAAGAACUGACAUUUAACUUUGAAGGUAUUUUUAACUUGUACAUUUUUAAAAUAUGUAUUUAUAUCUUAAUAAUAAAUAUUUCGAAGUUUU